GCGCCGGGUUUGUUGGGGGGUACUCGGCAGUGCAGCCAUGACUAUACUCCCCAAAAAGAAGCCGCCGCCUCCCGACGCCGACCCCGCCAACGAGCCGCCGCCGCCCGGGCCGAUGCCCCCGGCGCCGCGGCGCGGCGGAGGUGUGGGCGUGGGCGGCGGCGGCACGGGCGUGGGCGGCGGCGAUCGCGACCGUGACUCCGGCGUCGUGGGGGCCCGUCCGCGAGCUUCGCCACCGCCUCAAGGCCCGCUACCAGGACCGCCGGGCGCUCUUCAUCGCUGGGCGCUGGCCGUGCCGCCUGGUGCAGUGGCGGGUCCCCGGCCACAACAGGCUUCUCCACCUCCUUGCGGGGGCCCAGGUGGUCCCGGCGGCGGUCCCGGCGACGCGCUGGGCGCAGCGGCGGCGGGUGUGGGUGCCGCGGGCGUGGUGGUGGGUGUGGGUGGUGCCGUAGGCGUGGGCGGCUGCUGCUCCGGGCCUGGGCACAGCAAGCGGCGACGUCAAGCUCCCGGGGUUGGCGCGGUUGGCGGGGGCAGUCCCGAGCGUGAGGAGGUCGGCGCAGGCUACAACAGUGAGGACGAGUAUGAGGCGGCUGCAGCACGCAUCGAGGCUAUGGACCCUGCCACUGUCGAGCAGCAGGAGCAUUGGUUUGAAAAGGCCCUACGAGACAAGAAGGGCUUCAUCAUCAAGCAGAUGAAGGAGGAUGGCGCCUGUCUCUUCCGGGCUGUAGCUGACCAGGUGUAUGGAGACCAGGACAUGCAUGAGGUUGUGCGAAAGCAUUGCAUGGACUAUCUGAUGAAGAAUGCCGACUACUUCUCCAACUAUGUCACAGAGGACUUUACCACCUACAUUAACAGGAAGCGGAAAAACAAUUGCCAUGGCAACCACAUUGAGAUGCAGGCCAUGGCAGAGAUGUACAACCGUCCUGUGGAGGUGUACCAGUACAGCACAGGUACUUCUGCAGUGGAACCCAUCAACACAUUCCAUGGGAUACAUCAAAACGAGGACGAACCCAUUCGUGUUAGCUACCAUCGGAAUAUCCACUAUAAUUCAGUGGUGAAUCCUAACAAGGCCACCAUUGGUGUGGGGCUGGGCCUGCCAUCAUUCAAACCAGGGUUUGCAGAGCAGUCUCUGAUGAAGAAUGCCAUAAAAACAUCGGAGGAGUCAUGGAUUGAACAGCAGAUGCUAGAAGACAAGAAACGGGCCACAGACUGGGAGGCCACAAAUGAAGCCAUCGAGGAGCAGGUGGCUCGGGAAUCCUACCUGCAGUGGUUGCGGGAUCAGGAGAAACAGGCUCGCCAGGUCCGAGGCCCCAGCCAGCCCCGGAAAGCCAGCGCCACAUGCAGUUCGGCCACAGCAGCAGCCUCCAGUGGCCUGGAGGAGUGGACUAGCCGGUCCCCGCGGCAGCGGAGUUCAGCCUCGUCACCUGAGCACCCUGAGCUGCAUGCUGAAUUGGGCAUGAAGCCCCCUUCCCCAGGCACUGUUUUAGCUCUUGCCAAACCUCCUUCGCCCUGUGCGCCAGGUACAAGCAGUCAGUUCUCGGCAGGGGCCGACCGGGCAACUUCCCCCCUUGUGUCCCUCUACCCUGCUUUGGAGUGCCGGGCCCUCAUUCAGCAGAUGUCCCCCUCUGCCUUUGGUCUGAAUGACUGGGAUGAUGAUGAGAUCCUAGCUUCGGUGCUGGCAGUGUCCCAACAGGAAUACCUAGACAGUAUGAAGAAAAACAAAGUGCACAGAGACCCGCCCCCAGACAAGAGUUGAUGGAGACCCAGGGAUUGGACACCAUCUCCCAACCCCAGUACUCCUGCUCUCCGGUGCCACCUCACCUUCUUUGGCUUCUUCCCUCUUGCCUCCUUCUGUUCUUUCUGCUCUCCCCUCUUUUCCCUCCUCCUCACUUCCCUCUGGCUAGCCCACCCCUGCACUCUCUCUCAUUGCCGCUGCCACUAUCACCUGUCUCUCUGCCAGCUGAUGUGCCCUGUUGCCCCCCACCCCAUCCCGCACAGAACCAUCCCUGCAUUCCACAGGGGACUCGGGCAAGGGUGCCGAAGAUAGACAAGAGGCACACAGAGACAGACCAACUGGCAGCCAGGCAGCCCCAGAGGAGAGAGACAUUCAGACAGAGGAAAGUCUCCCUGCCCCUCAUUCCUUCCAAGAUGAGAAAAACUUGCCGCCACCCCCCGACACUGAUGCCAGGGAGGUGGGAGGAAGAAGUGGGAAAUUUCCCUUCCCAGUACCCCCAAGAACGUCUGAGCCUUCAAUGUUGAAUUUUUUCUUUAUUAAAAUUACUUUUAUCUUAUAAAAUCAACUAAUCAAAAAUGAUAUAGACGACAGCACUGGCUCUGUGAAGGUGGCAUCUUUCUGGGCAGGCAGGCCAUGGGGCAUGGAGGAGGGUGCAAAGAUAUGGGUUGCUGUCUUCUGGCCUCCAGCUGCAUGGAGGCCGGCCCAGGGUCUAGGGUGUGCACUGGGCAAGGGCAGGGCGGCAGGUGUCAGGCCGGCUUGGACAAUGAAACCCUGACCUUGCUGCAUUCCUUUUGCUUCCACCACCACUAGCUUCUUUGGAAUCUUGGGGUGGGGGUCAUCUUUGGGGAUUAUGGCUGCCACCCGGGAUUUGAGUGUAGGGAGUGUGGGAGCAGCCUUGGCAGAUGGGGCACCCGUGCCCUGCAGGUGUUGACAAGAUCCGCCAUCUGUAAUGUCCUUGGCACAAUAAAACCAAAUGUCAGUUUCCCUGAGCGACUCUGUUCUGUGUGGGGCAGGGGUUGGGCGGGCCUCUGGGCAGAGGAUGCAAUGGCACGGACCUUGGCUUGACCUCAGAGGUGUGAAUGCUCUCCAGCAGGGUCUGUCUGGGGGCCUGGAGUUUGUAUUUGAUUUGCUGCUUAUUAAACCUCCUUCUGGACCUAUUGCCACUGGAAAA